ACUCGCCUUGGGCGGCCGCGGAAGAGGCCCCGGGAUGAGGCCCCGGAGGACCGCGCGGGGCCUGCUCGGGCCGGGAAGCCGCGGAGUCGCGUGAGCACCGCCCGCCGGGCCCUGUGCCCCGCUUUCGGUCAGGCCUCCUGGGCCCGUGCGCAGUCCGGGCCGGCGGGGAACGCGGCUCCGGGCGUGUGGCGGGCGGAGAGGAAGCGUUUGUCGGCGCGGCACGUCGUGUGCUAGCCCGGGAGCGGCGGGCAGGGCUGGCCCCGAGGCCCGGGGCGGAGAUUCGUCGGUCCCCCGGGGCUGUGAGCGACCCCGGCAGCGAGGCCGCCGCCUCAACAGGUCCUCGCGGACCUCCGGGACAGUCCUGUGGGGUCCGCCGCCCUCCUCCCACCCAGAGCUCCGGGGAGAAGCUGCUGAGGACGCGGCUGGGACGAGGGGGGGCGCCGGGACCCGGACUUUCACUUGCAGUCUCUCCUCGCGCUUUUCUCCCGAGCCGGGAGGAGGAGGAGCUGGCGAUGUGUGCGCCGUGCCCGGUGUCUUUUGCAGAGUGACCGCCGUACCUGUUUUAUUCGUGUGUACCAGUGCUCGUUGUGCAGUGCGGUGUCCUAUGCGCUAAAGAAGUAAACAGGUCAUGGCACGUUUAACAAAAAGACGACAGGCGGAUACAAAAGCUAUCCAGCAUCUUUGGGCAGCCAUUGAGAUUAUACGGAACCAGAAGCAGAUUGCCAACAUUGACCGUAUUACAAAGUAUAUGUCUCGAGUCCACGGUAUGCACCCUAAAGAGACCACCCGUCAGCUGAGCUUAGCUGUGAAAGAUGGUCUUAUUGUCGAAACUCUAACAGUGGGCUGCAAAGGUUCAAAAGCUGGUAUUGAACAAGAAGGAUAUUGGUUGCCAGGAGAUGAGAUUGACUGGGAAACAGAAAAUCAUGACUGGUAUUGUUUUGAAUGCCAUUUGCCUGGAGAGGUGUUGAUAUGUGACCUGUGUUUUCGUGUGUAUCAUUCCAAGUGUUUGUCUGAUGAGUUCAGGCUUAGAGACAGCAGUAGUCCCUGGCAGUGCCCAGUUUGCAGGAGCAUUAAGAAGAAGAAUACAAACAAACAGGAGAUGGGCACAUACCUCAGAUUCAUUGUCUCCCGCAUGAAGGAGAGGGCUAUAGAUCUUAAUAAAAAGGGGAAGGACAAUAAACACCCGAUGUACAGGAGGCUGGUGCACUCAGCUGUGGACGUUCCCACCAUUCAAGAGAAAGUGAAUGAAGGGAAAUACCGAAGUUAUGAAGAGUUCAAAGCUGAUGCCCAAUUGCUUCUCCACAAUACCGUGAUUUUCUAUGGAGCAGACAGUGAGCAAGCUGACAUUGCGAGGAUGCUAUAUAAAGACACAUGUCAUGAGCUGGAUGAACUGCAGCUUUGCAAGAAUUGCUUUUACUUGUCAAAUGCUCGUCCUGACAACUGGUUCUGUUAUCCUUGUAUACCUAAUCAUGAGCUGGUUUGGGCUAAAAUGAAAGGUUUUGGGUUUUGGCCAGCCAAAGUCAUGCAGAAAGAAGACAAUCAAGUCGACGUUCGCUUCUUUGGCCACCACCACCAGAGGGCCUGGAUUCCUUCUGAAAACAUUCAAGAUAUCACAGUCAACAUUCAUCGGCUGCACGUGAAGCGCAGUAUGGGUUGGAAAAAGGCCUGUGAUGAGCUGGAGCUGCAUCAGCGUUUCCUACGAGAAGGGAGAUUUUGGAAAUCUAAGAAUGAGGACCGAGGUGAGGAAGAGGCAGAAUCCAGUAUCUCCUCCACCAGUAAUGAGCAGCUAAAGGUCACUCAAGAACCAAGAGCAAAGAAAGGACGACGUAAUCAAAGUGUGGAGCCCAAAAAGGAAGAACCAGAGCCUGAAACAGAAGCAGUAAGUUCUAGCCAGGAAAUACCCACGAUGCCUCAGCCCAUCGAAAAAGUCUCCGUGUCAACUCAGACAAAGAAGUUAAGUGCCUCUUCACCAAGAAUGCUGCAUCGGAGCACCCAGACCACAAACGACGGCGUGUGUCAGAGCAUGUGCCAUGACAAAUACACCAAGAUCUUCAAUGACUUCAAAGACCGGAUGAAGUCGGACCACAAGCGGGAGACAGAGCGUGUUGUCCGAGAAGCUCUGGAGAAGCUGCGUUCUGAAAUGGAAGAAGAAAAGAGACAAGCUGUAAAUAAAGCUGUAGCCAACAUGCAGGGUGAGAUGGACAGAAAAUGUAAGCAAGUAAAGGAAAAGUGUAAGGAAGAAUUUGUAGAAGAAAUCAAGAAGCUGGCAACACAGCACAAGCAACUGAUUUCUCAGACCAAGAAGAAGCAGUGGUGCUACAACUGUGAGGAGGAGGCCAUGUACCACUGCUGCUGGAACACAUCCUACUGCUCCAUCAAGUGCCAGCAGGAGCACUGGCACGCGGAGCACAAGCGCACCUGCCGCCGGAAAAGAUGAAGCUGGCCCUUCCCGGAGUCACCCCGAUGAUUACUCUUUUCAGACACAGCGGUUUUUGUUUCCAAGAAGCCAAAAUUGUUUAGAAUUUGCUUCCCAUUUUGCACCAGCCUUUAAACACUUUUCGUGAAGAAAUUUUGCACAGUAGUUUAAAUCUUUUGUUAAUGCUCCUCCGAAGUUUUUCAGGGGGUAAAAGUAACAUCAGUGGAGGGUAUUAUUUUAAAUAAAUUUUAAUUGAGAAUUUGUUGCAUUUUCAGCAAAUUUUAAAACAUUUUUAGGUUUUACAGAGAUUUUAACCUUUAAACAACAGAUCUUUAAAAAACAGGUGAAUACAAGUGAGUUUAACAAAGAAACAUUUAGAAUAGAUCUGAAUGUAAGAACUACAGAACUGUUUCAGAAAUAAAACAUACUACCUUGAUGUGACAUUUUUUUCUUAACCUUGUUGAGCUGGUUUUGUUCAGCUUAAUUUACUGUUCAAAGGCAUUAUCUGUUGGUCACACCAGUGGGUAUAUGAUUGAAUUUAGGGAACAGGGUUGACACAGCAGGGCUAGUCCUGCAUAUUUUUUCUUAAAUAUUUCCCAAUUGUGUUUUUCAUUAUUUCUUUUCAAUAUAUAACUUUUAUAACAAAUUAUUAGCUUUGAUCUUGUAGUUUAAAAUUGCAGGGAACUGGGGUAAUCUUUUACUGAGCUGGAUCUUAGAGAAAAUGAAUAUUUAAAUUUUAAAGUUUGCACAUUUCAUCUUUGUCCUAACAUGAGUGCUUGUAACAAAAUAAACAACAAAAACAAAGCCAAAAACUACCUUUAUCCAUAUGUGAAAUUAUAGAUGAGGCAUACGAAUUUGUUUAAUGCUUCCCUUCCCUUCCCACAUAUCAUCUCACUGCCUAUUAUCUGGUGUCACCUCAUGUAUCGUAAGUUAAUACUAAAAGAAGAGAAAGCACUUAAGUUUCACAGAAGCCGUUAUGUUUGUAGUAAUGGGUCAUUGCCUACUAAUGAACUCCAUCACUGUACACAGAAUGAAGAAUAAUGCAUGUUAAUUUUCUUGUAUUAAAGAUGCCGUGAUUUGUAAAAAGUCUGUAUUUUGCGGAAUGUCUGGAUUAAGAAGCAUUACCAAUAGGAAUGGAUCGAUAGUUGAAUAAUGAUUUUUUAUACAUAGAUAUAUAAAAUACAGCCAGGAAAACUUAAAUUACUUUUCUUUUAAAAUAUCUCACAAUUUAUGUGGUAUUUUUAAAGACUGAUCUUAGACCAAGUCAAAUUCCCAUUUAUCAUUUAGUUAUUUUUUGAGGUUAGAGAAUAAUUUGUACAUAUUUAUUUAGACCUUUGAUAUUUAUUAAAGCAAUUACUCACAAUGGAAGUGAAAGAAUCAGGAGAAAAGCCUUUUAAAAAGUAUUCUCCAGGUUUGUCAGGGUCACUCUAAAGAUAAAAAUGUAACUAAGUCUUCUGUGAAAUAUCAUCCAUCUAAUCUUGAUGCUGUUGCAGAUGGUGGUGACACAAGUUAAUUGACAAACUACUGCCAAAUGGUGCACAAUAUUUUGUAAAAAGUACCCAGUAGCCCCAUUUCAUACAAUGUACCUAAAUUAUGCAGUAACUUGGCAUCAUCGUUCCCUCCUUGUUGCUGUGUAAUUAGUCAGUGUUGCCACAGUGUGUGGCGCUGAUGGAGAUGUCAGAACCGAGAACACUUAACCUUCUUUGAUUGUUUUUCAAGUUUUAAGACUUCGAUCCACCCCUAUGAGAGCAAGUAAUUGUGGAAAUAUUUUUGGUGUAAAAUCAUUCCAGAGUAUGUAAUAUUUAACUGAUAGCUGCAUGAAAGUGAGAUUCGUGUUACUUUGGCUUUUCUGUCUCUGUUGACACGGUUGCACAUUUCCAAGUUACUACAGCGUGAAAACUGUGUGUUUAAAAAAAAACAAAAUUAAAAAAAGAGAUUGUGGCCUGGUUUUGUAAAAGUUUUAGGUAAAAUUACAAUUGAUUGUUUUAGGAAUCAUUAUUAAAAAUUUUCUGCAAAUCAUAAAGCUAUAUCGAGGUGUUGAGCUUAGCCACUAUGCACAUUGUAAUUAUUCAUUGUGGCUGUCCAGUUCUAUGAUGCAUUCUGGCAUUUUGUAAGCUGCUCUGACUAGCAAUAUAUAGAUUCAUUUAAUGUGUUAACAUUGGUUAAUAAAUGUAUUUAAAAAAAA